ACUGCGCCAUUUCCUGUCCAAAGCUGGGCGAAUCAGGUCGGUGCCGCGGGGUACCCCGGAAUCCCCCCUGGGAGCUGGUCCUGCACUGGCCUUCAGAGCCGAGCAGAGGACGCUGCUUUGGGCCCCAGAGCAUGGGAAGGUCUUGGCUGCGGUCUGGGACGGCUGCGGUCUGGGACCUGCAUGGAGGGCCCGGGACUUGCGGACGCCUGGGAGCGGUUGCUGGGCAACAGUGCGUGCGGCCUGGCCUCUUUGCGCCCGGCGGGCAGCGCGCGUCUGGGGCAGGCUCCGCGCGGGGCUCGGGCACAGGUCCCCGCUGCCGCAGCCCUACCGAGUGAAGCACUGAGCGCGGCGCCGCUUCGCCAUCACCUGGCUCUGGCCCUCUCACCCUAGCGUAGGGGGGCACUGGCCAGGCAGUGAGGACCCUGAGAUCCAUGCCCUGGGAGACAGAGGUUGUCUCCUGUCCAUGCACCCGCGCGCCUGCCUUCUAACCUUCAUACCGUUGGGCAGAUUAAUUCACUGGACUAGGCCUCUGUUCCGUGGGAGUUGAAAAGAUUUGACCUGGAAGAAACCCUAGCGAUUAUUCAGUUAAGCCGCAACCCCACCCCCUGUUUUAUAUAGGUAAGGGUGCUUCACGGUGAGGACUCGUCGCGUGCCUGGUGCUUUACAUCAGUCCCCAGAAUAGUCCUCGUAGUUUCUCUCUUACUGUUCCCAUAGUAUGGGUGAGGACUCUGAGGCUCGGAGAGGUUGUGAAUUUAGCCAGAAUCACACAGCUUGUAACUGGUGGAGAUGAGGACACUGAGACUCGAUUAAAUCACUCGUAGUUUGUUCGUGGCAGAUUACGUGUUAGAAGCGUGUUACACUACUAUGAAACCUGGCCAUAAAUGAGAAUCACCUGGAAAGUGUUUAAAAUCUAUAUUCGUGUCUGGGCAAUGUCCCGGGUUUACUGACUUGAAAUCUCGGGCUACGGCUGAGGAAGCUGUAUAUUUAACAAUCUUCCCGAUGAUUUUUAUGAUCUGUGGAUGAACCACUGAGUACUGCUGGGUACACCACGGGGCCUUCUCGCACAAAAACAACUGUAAAAUAAUAUCUGAGGUACCUAGAGCAGAAGAGACGCUGGGAUUCCGGUUCACAAUGGAUGCUGAUAAAGAGAAAGAUUUGCAGAAAUUUCUUAAAAAUGUGGAUGAAAUCUCCAAUUUAAUUCAGGAGAUGAAUUCUGAUGACCCAGUUGUGCAACAGAAAGCUGUCCUGGAGACAGAAAAGAGACUACUGCUUAUGGAGGAAGACCAGGAGGAGGAUGAAUGCAGGACCACCUUGAACAAGACUAUGAUCAGUCCUCCACAAACUGCUAUGAAGAGUGCAGAAGAAAUAAACUCAGAGGCCUUCUUGGCAUCUGUGGAGAAGGAUGCAAAGGAACGAGCCAAGAGAAGAAGGGAAAACAAAGUCUUGGCGGAUGCCCUAAAAGAAAAAGGGAAUGAAGCAUUUGCUGAAGGCAAUUAUGAAACAGCUAUCCUGCGCUACAGUGAGGGUUUGGAGAAGCUGAAGGACAUGAAAGUGCUGUACACCAACCGAGCCCAGGCUUAUAUGAAACUUGAGGACUAUGAGAAGGCACUGGUGGAUUGUGAGUGGGCUCUCAAGUGUGAUGAAAAAUGCACAAAAGCAUAUUUUCACAUGGGAAAAGCCAACCUGGCCCUGAAGAACUACAGUGUGUCUAGAGAGUGUUAUAAGAAGAUCUUAGAAAUAAACCCCAAGCUGCAAACCCAGGUGAAAGGUUACCUGAAUCAAGUAGAUCUUCAGGAAAAAGCAGACCUUCAAGAAAAGGAAGCCCACGAACUGCUGGAUUCAGGAAAGAACACAGCCGUGACCACCAAGAACCUCCUGGAGACCCUUUCCAAGCCUGACCAGAUCCCCUUGUUCUAUGCUGGGGGGAUUGAGAUCCUGACUGAAAUGAUAAAUGAGUGCACAGAACAAACUUUAUUCAGAAUGCACAAUGGAUUUAGUAUCAUCAGUGACAACGAGGUCAUAAGAAGGUGUUUUUCCACAGCAGGAAAUGAUGCAGUUGAAGAAAUGGUCUGUGUGUCUGUUCUCAAGCUCUGGCAAGCAGUGUGCAGCAGGAACGAGGAAAACCAGCGUGUGCUAGUGAUACACCAUGACAGGGCCAGGCUGUUGGCCGCCCUCUUGUCCUCCAAGGUCCUGGCCAUCCGGCAGCAGAGCUUUGCCCUGCUGCUGCAUCUCGCCCAGACUGAGAGCGGACGGAGCCUGAUCAUCAACCACCUUGACCUGACCAGAUUAUUGGAAGCGCUGGUGUCAUUUCUUGAUUUCUCGGAUAAGGAGGCCAACACUGCUAUGGGACUGUUCACAGACUUGGCUCUGGAAGAAAGAUUCCAAGUCUGGUUCCAGGCCAACCUUCCAGGUGUUCUCCCUGCACUCACAGGCGUUCUGAAGACAGAUCCCAAGGUAAGCAGCUCCUCGGCUCUGUGCCAGUGCAUUGCCAUCAUGGGAAACCUCAGUGCUGAGCCCACUACCCGAAGACACAUGGCGGCCUGUGAGGAAUUUGGGGAUGGCUGCUUGAGCCUCCUGGCCAGGUGUGAGGAGGAUGUGGACCUGUUCAGAGAGGUUAUCUACACACUCCUGGGACUCAUGAUGAACCUGUGUCUUCAGGCUCCCUUUGUCUCUGAGGUUUGGGCUGUGGAGGUGAGCAGAAGGUGCCUGUCUUUACUAAACAGCCAGGAUGGAGGAAUCCUGACAAGAGCUGCUGGUGUUCUGAGCCGGACCCUUUCUUCCUCUCUGAAAAUUGUUGAGGAGGCCUUGCGAGCAGGAGUGGUAAAGAAAAUGAUGAAAUUCCUGAAGACAGGAGGUGAGACUGCAUCACGUUAUGCUAUAAAGAUACUAGCUAUCUGCACGAAUAGUUAUCAUGAAGCUCGGGAAGAAGUAAUAAGACUGGAUAAAAAGUUGAGCGUUAUGAUGAAGCUGCUCAGCUCGGAGGAUGAGGUUCUGGUGGGCAACGCUGCCCUCUGCCUUGGUAACUGCAUGGAGGUGCCCAACGUUGCGUCUUCCCUGCUAAAGACGGACCUUUUGCAGGUCUUGUUAAAGCUUGCAGGCAGUGACACACAGAAGACGGCCGUGCAGGUGAACGCAGGCAUUGCUCUGGGGAAGCUGUGCACAGCUGAGCCCAGAUUUGCUGCUCAACUGAGAAAGCUUCAUGGCCUAGAAAUUCUCAACUCUACGAUGAAAUACAUCAGUGAUUCUUGAGAGAGACAGGGUUUGUGUGCAUUUGGGGAACACACAGAUGCACACCGUGUGUUGUUCCUAUGCUAAUAAAGACCUUUGAUGUAUCCA